AGAGACUGGACGGAGAGAGCGAGCCGCGGGCUGCCAGCGGCCCCCACCCGUCCCAGCUCGGCUUAGCCCCCGCGGACCCCUCCAGGCCGCGACCCCAGGGCGUCCUGUGCCGCCACGCCCUCCAUCUGUGUGGGUCCUCUGCUGGGCCCGCCCCUGGUCACAGCCAGACUGACUCAGUUUCCCUGGGAGGUCCCGCUCGAGCCCGUCCUUCCCCUCCCUCUGCCCGCCCCCAGCCCUCGCCCCACCCUCGGCGCCCGCACAUCUGCCUGCUCAGCUCCAGACGGCGCCCGGACCCCCGGGCGCGGGAUCCAGCCAGGUGGGAGCCCCGCAGAUGAGGUCUCUGAAGGUUGGUUCAGUGGCACGAUCUUGGCUCUGGGGCCCUGUUUCCGGCCCACAAACAUCACUUCCCCUGUCGGGUUCAAGCGAUUCUCCUGCCUCAGCCUCCCGAGUAGCUGGGAUUACAGGUGUGCCUGAACCAGUGCCAGCCUGCCCUGUCUGCAGCAUCGGCCUGAUGGGGUGGUGACUGAUCCCUCAGGGCUCCGGAGCCAUGUGGCCCAACGGCAGUUCCCUGGGGCCCUGUUUCCGGCCCACAAACAUUACCCUGGAGGAGAGACGGCUGAUCGCCUCGCCCUGGUUCGCCGCCUCCUUCUGCGUGGUGGGCCUGGCCUCCAACCUGCUGGCCCUGAGCGUGCUGGCGGGCGCGCGGCAGGGGGGUUCGCACACGCGCUCCUCCUUCCUCACCUUCCUCUGCGGCCUCGUCCUCACCGACUUCCUGGGGCUGCUGGUGACCGGUACCAUCGUGGUGUCCCAGCACGCCGCGCUCUUCGAGUGGCACGCCGUGGACCCUGGCUGCCGUCUCUGUCGCUUCAUGGGCGUCGUCAUGAUCUUCUUCGGCCUGUCCCCGCUGCUGCUGGGGGCCGCCAUGGCCUCAGAGCGCUACCUGGGUAUCACCCGGCCCUUCUCGCGCCCGGCGGUCGCCUCGCAGCGCCGCGCCUGGGCCACCGUGGGGCUGGUGUGGGCGGCCGCGCUGGCGCUGGGCCUGCUGCCCCUGCUGGGCGUGGGUCGCUACACCGUGCAAUACCCGGGGUCCUGGUGCUUCCUGACGCUGGGCGCCGAGUCCGGGGACGUGGCCUUCGGGCUGCUCUUCUCCAUGCUGGGCGGCCUCUCGGUCGGGCUGUCCUUCCUGCUGAACACGGUCAGCGUGGCCACCCUGUGCCACGUCUACCACGGGCAGGAGGCGGCCCAGCAGCGUCCCCGGGACUCCGAGGUGGAGAUGAUGGCUCAGCUCCUGGGGAUCAUGGUGGUGGCCAGCGUGUGUUGGCUGCCCCUUCUGGUCUUCAUCGCCCAGACAGUGCUGCGAAACCCGCCUGCCAUGAGCCCCGCCGGGCAGCUGUCCCGCACCACGGAGAAGGAGCUGCUCAUCUACUUGCGCGUGGCCACCUGGAACCAGAUCCUGGACCCCUGGGUGUAUAUCCUGUUCCGCCGCGCCGUGCUCCGGCGUCUCCAGCCUCGCCUCAGCACCCGGCCCAGGUCGCUGUCCCUCCAGCCCCAGCUCACGCAGCGCUCCGGGCUGCAGUAGGAAGUGGACAGAGCGCCCCUCCCGCGCCUUUCCGCGGAGCCCUUGGCCCCUCGGACAGCCCAUCUGCCUGUUCUGAGGAUUCAGGGGCUGGGGGUGCUGGAUGGACAGUGGGCAUCAGCAGCAGGGUUUUGGGUUGACCCCAAUCCAACCCGGGGACCCCCAACUCCUCCCUGAUCCUUUUACCAAGCACUCUCCCUUCCUCGGCCCCUUUUUCCCAUCCAGAGCUCCCACCCCUUCUCUGCGUCCCUCCCAACCCCAGGAAGGGCAUGCAGACAUUGGAAGAGGGUCUUGCAUUGCUAUUUUUUUUUUUAGACGGAGUCUUGCUCUGUCCCCCAGGCUGGAGUGCAGUGGCGCAAUCUCAGCUCACUGCAACCUCCACCUCCCGGGUUCAAGCGAUUCUCCUGCCUCAGCCUCCUGAGUAGCUGGGACUAUAGGCGCGCGCCACCACGCCCGGCUAAUUUUUGUAUUUUUAGUAGAGACGGGGUUUCACCGUGUUGGCCAGGCUGGUCUUGAACUCCUGACCUCAGGUGAUUCACCAGCCUCAGCCUCCCAAAGUGCUGGGAUCACAGGCAUGAACCACCACACCUGGCCAUUUUUUUUUUUUUUUUUAGACGGAGUCUCACUCUGUGGCCCAGCCUGGAGUACAGUGGCACGAUCUCGGCUCACUGCAACCUCCGCCUCCCGGGUUCAAGCGAUUCUCGUGCCUCAGCCUCCCGAGCAGCUGGGAUUACAGGCGUAAGCCACUGCGCCCGGCCUUGCAUGCUCUUUGACCCUGAAUUUGACCUACUUGCUGGGGUACAGUUGCUUCCUUUUGAACCUCCAACAGGGAAGGCUCUGUCCAGAAAGGAUUGAAUGUGAACGGGGGCACCCCCUUUUCUUGCCAAAAUAUAUCUCUGCCUUUGGUUUUAUUUUCCUUUGGGUCCAGAAGUUUUCAAUCUCUGGAGUUUGUGCAUUGGGCCUCACCCGGAGCAGACGAGGGCAGGGCUGGGAAGGAUGGGGAGGGACAUAGAGGAUUCGGUUCCUCCCCCACCUUGUUUCUUGAGUGUUUCCUAAUCACUUGAUGGGUGGUACCACCUAGAAUUCUUCCAGCAGCCUGUAAUGGGAGGGCUACAGGUUAGCCCUGGAACCUGCAAUCAAACCACCUUUGAAUCUGUGUGUCAUUAAAAGUAGAUAUAAAUGGG